UCAGGUGAUCCGCCUGUCUCGACCUUCCAAAGUGCUGGGAUUAUAGGCGUGAGCCACUGCGCCCCUCCCUGUUGAUGCUUUUUGAUGAAAUACCCAAACUUGCACGUCUCCCAGAAUGUGAAGGCCAAGGCUGGGAACAGGCCUGUCAAAUGUUCCGGGUGGUUUGAUGCAGCCUCUGUGACCGUCAAGGCCUCUUACCCACUACCAAGGUACAGAACCCACUAGAUAAAACAAGUCAAGAAUCCAACCCAAGCCCGCAUGCUUUGGCAGAAAUUUUUAAGAUGGGGUGGGGAGUACAGGAAGGACUUCCUUCGCAUGGACUGAAAAGCCCUUUUUGUUCUAAAGGAGUAAUGACUUUGAAGAGGCCUAAUUUUUUGGUUAGGUUUCCAGACUAAAUAUUUGUUUCUUGAGCAGCAGCGGGUCCUCUGAGGUGAAGUGGUAAACACUUUUGGCCUAUGACUGCAGGUAAUAAAAAUCUGUCCGGGCUGCCCGAGGGGAGGGGCGCCGGUAAAGCCGUAGCUGCAGCGAAGCCCCGCGUCUGCCGCUGCCGGAGCCUGGCUCUCCUCUUACGCGGGGGGCUGCGGGCAAUUGGGGCCGACAACUUGCGGUCCCGCCUUGGGACGCAUGCUUGCUCGAGAGCUGGGGCUGCAGGGUGCAGUGGGACAGUAGGACCGCGAAAGCCUGGGCUUCGAGCCUCGGGCUCCCUGUCUUCAGGCGAAGUGCGGUUUCCACGGGUGCAGGUUUCGCUGCAUAAGGGAAGACUCAGAUUUCGAGCCCUCGGCAGGCCAGCUUCUAGCUCUCUGUCCCUUCCGGGUCUCUCCGGUUGCUUCUGUCUUUCCUCCUCCCACUCCCGUCGCAAUCCCGCGCCCCACGGAGGAAGGUCGUGGUGCGGGAGUUGGGGGAUACUUUCUUCCUGGGCUCGGUCUACGCAGACCCAUCGCCUGCCUCGAGUUCCUGUGCCCUCAGACGCCACGGGAAAACUUGCAGGGACAUCUAGCGCCAGGCGUGGGGAACUGCGCGCCGCCGGGCCGGGAAGUGGAGCCGAACACUGCCCCUCCGCCUCCCUUUCGGCUCCCCCCUUCGUGCUUGGGCACUUUCCUCACCUUCAUCCCUUUGCCCUGCCGGUAAGGACAAUGUGGAUUCCCCAUAGAGACAAUGGACUCUGCGGAAUGGAGAUAGGGGAUGUGGCUCUAAAUCAGCCGGACAUGUGCGUCUACCGAAGAGGGAGGAAGAAGAGAGUGCCUUACACCAAACUGCAGCUUAAAGAACUGGAGAACGAGUAUGCCAUUAACAAAUUCAUUAACAAGGACAAGCGGCGGCGUAUCUCGGCUGCUACGAACCUAUCUGAGAGACAAGUGACCAUUUGGUUUCAGAACCGAAGAGUGAAGGACAAGAAAAUUGUCUCCAAGCUCAAAGAUACUGUCUCCUGAUGUGGUCCAGGUUGGCCACAGACAGCUUAGAAGCCAUUCGGUUGUCUCCAAAAGGCCUUUGGAAAGACUUGAAUAUGUAUUUAAUUCCCCCCACCCCCUGCCAAUGGUGGCAAAUUUUGUGAAUUGUUUUUCUCUCUUCCCCUUAUCUGGCUCUAAAACCUUCUGCUGCCCAACCUGACUUUGUAGUUCUGAUUUUUACUUGUUUAUUAUUGGUUUUGUUCUUGCCUAGGGUUUUUAAAAUAUCUGUUUUUAAUGUUUUGUUUCUCCCUCCAGGCCAGUAUAAAGGGACUUGAAGUAUUUUUUAAUAAUCCGCCCCCCAAUGAACUUCAGAAGUGCCAUUCUGAUUUAAGGGUUUUUUUAAAAAAUUACUUUAUUUGUUCAUUCCCAGCACUGAUUAUCUUCAUAAUCCAUUAGGACAGAAUGGUUUUCAGUCGUUCAUAUCCUGUAAUUAGGUAAUUGAAUCAUUAGCUCUCAGCAGUUGCCCUGAGGCAAGUGGAAAGGCAGGCAGUGCUCUGGGGUCACCGAGAAAGUCUAAAAACAGGAGGCUGAAGGUACUGUGAUGGCUUUAAAAAUGGCCACCUUAUUAAAUAGGGAUUGUAUCAAUAUUGAAAUGAAGACAAUCUUUCCAACUUUGGGUGUUUCACUUGCUGUUUUAAUUGUUUGUUUUUAACACUUUGUAGGUUUGUGUUUUCAUAAUCUUUAAUUUGAAACUCAUGUGUCCUCAUGGAUCGUGGAUGCCUUCAUUUCUUGAGCUCUCAAUGCAGACAUUUAAAUGGCUGCAAUCAGUAGAGUGACCCGCGGAUGGCAUAAAUGCACCUCCUUUUCUUGGCCUUGGAUCUAUGGGUCUGGGAUUGUGGUCAUCUCCUCAAUCCUCAAAAAGAGGCUGAAUCAAUGUGGCCGUGGGUGGGAACUUACAUACAGAACCCAAUGAAGAACUUGACUGUCUAAACAAGGGGGCCUCGCAUGGAGCUGUAAAGCAUCUAACAAAUAUGAAAAAUGUGAAGUUCCAAGGUCCAAGAAGAAAAAUAAUGAUGUUUCUGAAAGUGAUGAUAAAUAAUUACUUUUAAAGUGCUGCAUAUUUAUACAAUUGAGAGAUUAUUUUUGUAAAUGCAAUGUCUGUGAGCUGGGAUACAUGGGCAGUGCUUCAGACAUUUAAAAAUCACUUUUUACUCCUAGGGAGAUGCCAAUAAACAGAACUCUUUUGUUUCUUCUGA